GGUCGCCGCGGUGCUGCUGCUCAGUGGGAGCGGGUCUUCGCAACUGUCUCCGCGUGGCGCGCGCCUCUAGCCGCCCUUCCCCUGGCGGCUACGGCCGGAGGGAGCGGAGGCGAGCGGGAGUCGGGCUCCAUGGAGAGCGGCGGACAACUGGGCAGAGGCGGAGCUUUCAUCUCGGCACCCUGGUUCCAGUGACCCGCGCUAGCGUCCCGUCCCGCCCGCGUCGGAGCGGCCGCCGGCCCCGGGACUGACCGGCCUCGCCGCACCUCCCGCACCGACUAGCGCUCCCGGGCGCUCCUGCGCCCGACUCGCCCUCGCCCCCACUCCCCGGCGGGGUGGCGGCGGCCGGGCCCCCACGGCGGCGGCCGGAGCAGCAGCAGCAGCAGCAGGAGCCCGCCUCUAUGAUGAAGUUCAAGCCCAACCAGACGCGGACCUACGACCGCGAGGGCUUCAAGAAGCGGGCGGCGUGCCUGUGCUUCCGGAGCGAGCAGGAGGACGAGGUGCUGCUGGUGAGUAGCAGCCGGUACCCAGACCAGUGGAUUGUCCCAGGAGGAGGAAUGGAACCCGAGGAGGAACCUGGCGGUGCUGCCGUGAGGGAAGUUUAUGAGGAGGCUGGAGUCAAAGGAAAACUAGGCAGACUUCUGGGCAUAUUUGAGCAGAACCAAGACCGAAAGCACAGAACAUAUGUUUAUGUUCUAACAGUCACUGAAAUAUUAGAAGAUUGGGAAGAUUCUGUUAAUAUUGGAAGGAAGAGAGAGUGGUUCAAAGUAGAAGAUGCUAUCAAAGUUCUCCAGUGUCAUAAACCUGUACAUGCAGAGUAUCUGGAAAAGCUAAAGCUGGGUUGUUCCCCAGCCAAUGGAAAUUCUACAGUCCCUUCCCUUCCGGAUAAUAAUGCCUUGUUUGUAACCGCUGCACAGACCUCUGGGUUGCCAUCUAGUGUAAGAUAGAGAGAACUGGGUAGGCCUCUCCCACCAUGUGCAGUCUCAUGGGGAGAGGCUUCUUUCGUUUCCUCGUCAAACAUCUGAUUGACGCUUGCAAACUGUCUGAAUUUGCCAUGCAAGGUUUUCAAACAAUUUGCAUGUUUUUCAGAUGCUUUCAAAUCUUUUUUUAAAAAAAUAGUGUAAAAUAUUUUAAUAAGCCAAAGCCAUGUGGAAUUUUUGUUUAGAUGCCUUAACUGUGCCACACCCCACAACCCCCUAUAUUAUUUUGGUUGUCUAUUUCUCACAGCAUAUUUUCAGUUUUUUGUCCAUUUGACAUCAGUCUGUGGUUUAUUUUGUCAUCAGAUUACUUGUGGGUAUACCUACCCCAAAAUUGUUUUCUCAUUCACAGCAUUAGCAUAUUCAGCAAAUCCAUCUGUGGUGGGAAUUAAAAAUAUUAUUGGUAUUAAAGAAAUCCAUUCACCCCAAAACUUGUUUUACAGGAUUACAAUUUUAAUUCAAAAUUUCCAGAUUUGGGCUAUUUCUGUAUGAUCCAAUAACUUAUUUUGUCACAGGGCUUAAUUUGCCAUUUUUGGGGAUUUGUCGACUCAUUUUGUCUGAAUUUUCACAACUGGUAUUAUGUCACUAGCUACCUGAUACGGCUAUUUCCCUUAUAACUCAAUAGUACCUUAACACAAAGUAUAACUCUGUAGAGUUGGUGAAUAUUUUAGGGAAAUAUUAGCAAAAUGCAUGUAGUAAAGACAUCUUAUGAAAACUGUAUUCAUGGAAUUUGAUUUAGCAUGCUCAGUUGCCAGUUCCCAUUAUCGAUACUCUUUCUUUGCAGAAUACCUUAGAACCGUUAUUUCCCUCAGUGUAGAUUGCUCUUAAAAUGUAUUCAGUUAUUUAGUGGCCCCCACAGGAGUGGAGUCUUGAAAUCUAAUUCUAAAUGCCAGUCAGUGAUGAUCGCAUCACAGUUGAGUGAAAUGGCCUUCCUGUUCAGCUGUUAGAGACUGAAGAUUGUUAGGGCACCUUAGAAUGUCUCAUCUUUUCUAGGUUGUCAACAGGUACUAUUUGUCACAUAACUAACUUUCGAGGCACUGGAACAUACCUGAACUAAGAAUUAAAUCUUUUACUUUAUACUCACUUAAAAUCAAGAAUCCCAUCUAAAACACAUAGGUACCUUAUCUGAAACUCUUGCACUUCCCCAACCAGGGCAGAAAUGAGGUGGGAGAAGUUUGACUAAAAUGAGGGAUGGGGGAAAGUAAAAGAUGUUUUUUUUUUUUUGAGACUCGCUUUGUCACCCAGGCUGGAGUGCAAUGGCACAAUCUCAACUCACCGCAACCUCCGCCUCCCGGGUUCAAGCGAUUCUCCUGCCUCAGCCUCCCGAGUAGUUGGGAUUACAGGCGCCUGCCUCCAUGCCUGGCUAAUUUUGUAUUUUUAGUAGAGACAGGGUUUCUUCAUGUUGGUCAGGCUGGUCUCAAACUCCUAACCUCGUGAUCCGCCUGCCUCGACCUCCCAAAGUGCUGGGAUUACAGGCAUGAGCCACCAUGCCCAGCCAAAGAUCAUUUUUUUAUAUAGACUUCAGCCCUUUGUAAAUAUUGUAACUGGGGAGUAUAGAGUAGAAAAAAAGUAUAGUUAAAACAUUUGUUCUACAAAUUAACCUUUAAAAAUAUAAUUACUGCUAAAAAUAGAGUGCUGUUACACUUAAGGAAAAUUAGUGCCAUUUUGGAAAUGAGAUCUUGUGCCAUAAAUACAGCUGAACUGAAUAUAAAUGUUCACAAAUUAAUGCUGUCAAAGGAAUGAGUAAAGCAGAAAAACUUUUAACCAGCAACAUUUCAAGUACGUAGUGUGAUCAAACAUGAUCAUCCAGAAUUUUUAUAUUUUUUUCUUUGUACAGAGGUUACAUAUUCUGGGUGUUCUUUUAUAAAGGAAACAUUUUAAAUCCCACAAAUUGACACUUUCUAUCUUCAAUGGACUAAGAUUUUUUUGGUCAGUAAUCUCUGAAAUUUCCUUAAAUUAUAUACUUAACAUAGCAGAGAAACUGGAUUGUUUUUGUAUAUAAGACUGCUUCCACCUGAAAUGCUGUCAUAAGUACUGGGGGGGUGGGGGAGUGCCCAUCUUGUACAUGAUAUUCUUAGAGGUAAUAAGGUAAUGAUGCAUGAAUUUAUUUUAUAAACUCUUGGACUAUGUAUUUGACAUGUAAAAUAUGUACAGUAUUAACGUCAACCAUCUCUUUAAAGUUAGCCUAUAAAUAUUGUUGUAUAAUUUUCUUUGGUCAGAAACACUUGGACUGAAUAGUGACACUCGGUAAGGAUUUUCAGUGCCAUUUAGCAAAACGUCUUUAGUCUAUGCAACUAGCAAAAAUCUGCAUAAUGCAACAACACAGUUUUCACACUUCAAAUUUUACAUGAGGGGUUCUUCACGAUUCUCCUGGAACCCAGUCUAGCAAAAUGAGAGGAAAGGCCCUAGGGAGAUUUAUUUCUGUUAAAUAGUUAACUCUGCUGAGUAUGACAAAUAGUGUCUACUAUCUCAACCCUCCAAAAUUUGCAGAGUGUUGGGACUGUCAUUUGUGAUUUUUUUUUUUUUUUUUUGGUGGGGUAGUUGAAUAAAAUUGGGCAGCUAAAUUUUUCAGUUCCAUGUGCCUCCCAAAUAAAAAACAGAAAAUAAGUAGUUUUUGUGAAUUGACUUGCAGACAAAGUAGAAACUGUGCUGCAUGAUGUUAUUUUGUAAACAGAUGACAUUUUCUGACCAGGCACAUGCCAUCCAAUUUUCUGUCAAUCACACUGUUGUAUAAAGCAGCAGAACUGAAGGGGAAAAAUGAUUGUUGUAUACACUGAAUUGCUUUGCAUGGUCUCAUUUGAGAUAAUUGAUGUAAGAAUCCUGACUUUUUUAUAUUUGGAAACAUCAAAUAAAAAUGGAAAAAAUGAUCAUGGCUUUAAAAAAAAAACAAAAACACACACACAUGAACUCAGAUUUGCAAACCAGGUUUCUGAAACUUUGGGUAAGGUGUAUGCUUUUAACUUUGAAAUGUAUAAACACCCAGCGGAAACGUAUACCUUUCAGUGCAUAGUGCAUUGUGUGCUUACCCUGGGUUGUUUAAACUUGUGUUCAAAUAUUCCCCCUCCAAGUGAAAGCCUGUCGGGAAUUCCACAGUAACACCUUUACUGUUCUCCCAUUGAUGAUCAUAUACGUUACCUCUUCCUAGCGGUACAUUUGUAUGAUCCUUACUACUGGAAUUACCGGGUUAAAAGGAAAUGCUUACCACUAAGAUGUCAGUAUUCUCCUCAUGGAUAUUUUCAGUCUCAAUGUUGCCAGUCUAAUAGUAUAGUAUGUGGUUGCUUUACUGCUGUUCUCCCCACCCCCGUGGAGUUGUGUCAUUAUUUUAAUGAAUGUGAGCUCUUGACUUACUCUAGAAUUCUAAUACAGAUACUUUCUGCACUAGUAUCACUUUUAUUAUUGCAGUUCCAUUUAAAAGCAUAACUGGCUAAGUCACCGCCCCACCCGCCGCAUUACAUUUCCUAAAACAUACUGCUGCCAAAGACCAACUGUAGAAUCCUUAAGUCCUGUUCAAGUGUCACUUCAUUUUUUAUUAGGGGUUUCUUAGUUGGAGGGCAUGAGAAACUUGGCCCUUUCCAAUGUUGUCUUCACAUUGGAGUAUAAGAAUUCUCUAUAGGACUCUUUAAUUUUUUUUUUUUUUUGGUAGAGAUGGGGUCUUGCUGUGUUGCCCAGGCUGGUCUCAAACUCCUAGGCUUAAGCAGUCCUCCAGCCUCAGCCUUCUCAAAGUGCUAGGAUGAUUGGCAUGAGCCACCUCGUCUGGCCUGCAGGUCUUUUUAAGCAUUUGCUGUUCAAUAAUAAGCAUCUUCUUUAUGCCUAGUAUUUGUGAUAAGAGCACAAAACAAUUUUCUAAUCUCAAAGAGCUUAUAUUCUAGUGGGGUAGAGAUAAGUGAUUUAUCUUGGUGUAGUUUUGGCUUUUUUGUUUGUUUUUUUGAGACAGCAUCUCACACUGUCGCCCAGGCUGGAGUGCAGUGGUGCAAUCUCAGCUUACUGUAACCUCCGCCUGCCAGGUUCAAGCGAUUCUCCUGCCUCAUCCUCCCGAGGAGCUGGGAUCACAGGCGCCUGCCACCACGCCCGGCUAAUUUUUUUGUAUUUUUAGUAGAGACGGGGUUUCACCAUAUUGGCCAGGCUGGUCUCAAACUCCUGACCUCGUGAUCCGCCUGCCUCGGCCUCCCUAAGUGCUGGGAUUAUGGGCGUGAACCACCGCACCUGGCCUAUCUUGGUGUUUUUACAUCCUUCAGUAUUUUUCAAGGUUUUACAGCUUUUUUAUCUAUAGACUUAUACCAUCUUCAAAAGCAAUACAAUUUUAUUUGUAGACGUGAUUUCCCCCACCAAAUGCACAUUUUAUGGAGCUCUAGGACAAAAGUCAGGAUGAAAAGUAAUCUAUCGCUGGUGCUACUUUAAUACCUUCCUGACUGGUGCCACUGGCUAAAUUCUAGCAGUACGAUGAGAGGGCCAUUAAGGCCUAUCUUAGCAAGCAAGACAUUAUAGCAAAGACCUAAACACUCAAAGGUUCAACGUCUUCUAGCCAGGGAACUAUUCUCUAAUUCUUCCACCUUGAUAUGAUUUCAGCAAAUUCUGAUAACCCGGUAUUACUCUUAAUGCAUUUUUGUAACAUUUGACAAACAUCUCCCAAUAUGUAGACUCCCACUCUCCUGAUGCUAAUCAGUAUCAGACAAUGGAAGUAAAUUUUCCUGCUUUUCUCAACUUUUCCUCAAAUUCAUGUUAGUGAAGUACUUUCAUUUGGCCAUCAUUAUUUAUCAACCUUAAGAAACAUGCCUAUUGACGAAGUAAAUAUACUAGGAAUUCAACGUAUCUACGGGAAUGUGGACAAAGACAUAUACCAAGACAAGGCACUAGAGUGAAAAGCCAUUAAAAUAAAAUGCUCAGCAGCAAAGGAUUUGUAAUGGUUAACUUGCAAUAUAUCCAUAUGGUGUAAUAUUACAGUCAUUAGAAAUGACAUUUGCGUAAGGAUCUGAGUGGAAACUGAUACAGCCUGUCGGAGAGCUACUGAGUAGUAUUUUAUCACAGCUGCAUACAUACCCUUUCACCCAACAGUUCCACUCCUGGGAGUCUAGUCAACAAAUGGACAAGUUGCACAACCAAGCUAUGGUCAAAUAUGUGUGUUGUAGGAUUUAUGAAACUGGUACCAAUUUAAUAUUCAAAUGUGAUUAAGUCAUGGCAAUCUAUUUACUGGAUACUUUGUGGUUACCAAAGAGCUAUGUGCUGCCACAGGGAGUCCUUUCAAUAGUGAUUGAAAAAGGCAGAACACUACUAGACAGAACUACCUGUUUUAUGCAUGUAUUGGCAUACACUGAAAAAGCUUAGUCACUUAAAAUGAGGUUGUACAGAUUGUAGAUUUUGUUUUUAAACGCCUGUAUGGUUUAAAAAAUGUUUUGGGAAAUAGACAUGAGCAGGGCAGAGAACUACAACCUACAGGCCAAACCCCACCCCACUGCCUGUUUGUACGGCCAACAAGUUUAAAAUUUUUUUAAUGUUUUAGGUUUUUUUUUUUUUAAAAAAAAUACUAUGCCCAUUUGUUUACAAAUCGUCUGUGGGUGCUUUCUCACUACAAUGGCAGAAUUCAGUAGUUGAGACAGACCUAUGGUCCACAAAGGCCGAAAUAUUUACUGUUUUAGGAGAAAAAAACAACAUGAAUUGUAAUAACUUGGACUUACUUGGUUGCUCAGUCCUGAUGUGUCCUGUUAAAACCUAAGAGAAACAGCACCAAGUUCAAUCUAGUGCAAUCAGCCUAUCACAUCUAAGCUGCUUUUGCCAGAUCUGAUAUCUACUCCCGACCUUAAGCCAGGAGACUUUGUAAACUUACUAGGUUAUAAUAAAACUUAAGAACUAUCGAUAUUUACUAAUCUACAUCAUGGAACUAUUUCAAAAGCAGUCAUAUGGUAAGAUGGAUCAGGAGUCUUUAAAAAUAAAACUGAGAAAGAAAAAUCAUGUGAUCAAUUCAGUAGUAGAGACAGAGGUUGGUAUCAAGUCUAUGUUCAUACACUUACCAGUGCCACCCAGCAGGGCCAUACAAGACACAUGAAAUGAGAUCAGCUCAAGGGUGACAAGAUGAAACUGGGAGAGGGCCGGGGAGACCCGAACUCUUAAUAUUGGAUUCCACACAAGAGGAAAAAUUUUAGUCCAGCUCCCAGCAUGGCAGCUAAUGGCAAGUUAGUACCAUAAAGCCAACUCUUGGAAUAUACCUGACUUCCACGAUAAAAUGGAGAUGAGUGCAGGGGUGAGUGUAUAGUUAAGAAAACAAACAAUAUAUUACUAGUCCAGGUGGUAGAUGACAGAUUUUUAUUAUUUACACUUCUCUCAAAUUAUUACAUUCAGCAUGUUUUGCUUUUUAUGUUAUUUAAAGUAUAAACCCUCAUAUAAUUCCCUAAGAUGGGUGGCAUGCCAAGUAGCUAAAUGAAAUAUCAUCCCAGCCCAAAAGUACUUAUUCGAAUGAAAUAUUACAUUUUUCUUAAAUAAAGCAAUAAAUUAGGUACCCUAUUAUCAUGGUAUUUUCUUUUUUGGCCAGCUUUUCUAGAUAAGGUUGUAUUGCUACUGCAACUAACAAAAAAGAUGUGGCAGGGCUGGGCACGGUGGCUCACGCCUGUAAUCCCAGCACUUUGGGAGGCCGAGGCGGGCAGAUCACGAGGUCAGGAGAUGGAGACCAUCCUGGCCCAACAUGGUGAAACCCCGUCUCUACUAAAAAUACAAAAAAUUAGCCAGGUGUGGUGGCAGGUGUCUGUAGUCCCAGCUCCUCAGGAGGCUGAGGCAGGAGAAUCGCUUGAACGCGGGAGGCAGAACCUGCAGUGAGCCAAGAUCAUGCCACAGCACUCCAGCCUAAACUACAGAGCUAGAAAGUGGCUAGAGCAGCCAAAAAAAAAAAAAAAAAAAAAAAAAAAAAAGGUUCCUGAACCAUUCAACAGAAAAAUGAGGCCUAUUCCUAUCAUUUCCUCGAUCCAAUUUAGUUCCACUUAGGUCACUGUGUUUAUAAUGUCUUUUAGGACAGAUUUCCUUCCCCAUUCUCCAUCAAACAACCAUAGCACCUGUGACUUUUAUCUGUUGGUUUGUAUUUAAUCUUAUUUUUAAGUGCUUCUUUGAAAUUGUUUUACAAGUACAUUCUUGGUCUAGAGUAAGGUUCUAUAUAGUUGGCCCUCCAUAUCCAUGGGUUCCACUUCCGUGGAUUCAAACAACCAGACAAAAUAUUCCAAAAAACAUUGUGUCUGUAGUCAACAUGUAUAUUUUUGUCAUUAUUCCUUAAACAAUAGUGUAACUAUUUACAUAGCACUUACAUUAUAAUAGGUAUUAUAAGUAAUCUAAAUAUUAACAUAAGCGGGAGGAUUUGUGUAGAUUGUAUGCAUAUACAACAUCAUUUUAUUCCAGAGACUUGAGCAUCUGCGAAUUUGGAUAUCCAAAGGAAGUCCUAGAACCAGUUCCCGACAAAUACCAAGAGAUGACUUUACUUUAGACCUAAGAUCUUGCUAGACAGCCUUUGAGAGGAUGAAGGAUAACUAGAGCAGAAGCAAAUCGCAGCGAAGUAGACUACAACAAUCAAGUCAAAAAACAUAAAGCUCCUAUCAACACCUCAAGAUUUUAGAAAAGCCUCUUAACGGGCAAUUUUCUUUUAAAUAAAGACUGGGUCCCACUAUGUUAGCCAGGCUGGUCACAAACUCCUGGACUCAAGUGAUCCUCCUGCCUUGGCCUCCUAAAGUGCUGGGAUUACAGGCAUGAGCCACUGUGCCCGGCCUGGGCAGUCGAUUUUCAGGAAGCCACUUAAUGUUCAGAUUCUUUUCUUCUCUCCCAGGACUUUGCAGAUGCUGCUGUUCCCUCUGCCUGGAGAUGUUCAUCUGGCCUGAAUCCAAAAGUCUGUCCAAGUUACUUCUCUUUUCCAUGACAGAGUUACAACUAUUUGUCUGUCCCCCUUCCCCAUUAGAGUAUAUGGUCCCCAAAGGAAAGCCCCAUGCCAUUCACUCACCACCUAAUCAUCCCCAACAACUAGUGGGCAAACAUGAAACACUUUUGUUGAAUAAUGUGUUUCCUUUAGCCCAGGGAUUACAAAGUCAAAGGCUUACAAGGGGGAAGGACUAGCAGGUGUGCUCGGAGGGGACUCUAGCCAACUGGAGAGUAACUGGUGAGAAGACAAUGACAUGCUCUUAGGGUGUCUGCUACUCAGAUCCUCUCAGUUAAGUCCCGUGCACAAAGGUGGGUCAGGUCUACUGUUGCCAGAUCUUCAGAUCAUUCAAAAGUUACCCGAAUUCUGGAUUUUCAUGCAAAUCUCCCAAUUUUUAAAAAUGUUGGCAUCAAAUUCAGAAUGUUUUAACCAGCCACACUGUGUGGGCCAGGGAAAACAGGCCCAAAGGCCAGGUGAAGCUGCAGUUUUCAACUGCUGCCUUGGCCUCUCCCAGAGCCCCUUAAGUCCUAAGAAGGCUCAGUCAACACACUGGCACUCGUUUCAUCCCACUGGUUGAGAAAGCAAGUCUUAGCAAAGUAAUGGGGGAGUCUUACCAAAACUGCAAAGGAAAAAAAUAUGAUACCAUGAAAUUAGAAAUUCACUGCAUUUGAAAUGAAAAUGACUUAUUUCUGUACUUCUAUAACUCACAAAUUUAGCAGACAUCAUUUAGACAUUUUUGUAGUGCAACAGAUUUAAAUCUGGAAUUUCAUGGUUUGUAAAUCACUAUGUGAUACUAGCUAUAACCAUGAGCAAUAUUACGGGCAGUAAAUGUUGAUUUCUAUUUCGUUUCUUGAA